ACCAGACCGCGGACGUCUGUAAUCUCAGAGGCUUGUUUGCUGAGGGUGCCUGCGCAGCUGCGACGGCUGCUGGUUUUGAAACAUGAAUCUUUCGCUCGUCCUGGCUGCCUUUUGCUUGGGAAUAGCCUCCGCUGUUCCAAAAUUUGACCAAAAUUUGGAUACAAAGUGGUACCAGUGGAAGGCAACACACAGAAGAUUAUAUGGCGCGAAUGAAGAAGGAUGGAGGAGAGCAGUGUGGGAAAAGAAUAUGAAAAUGAUUGAACUGCACAAUGGGGAAUACAGCCAAGGGAAACAUGGCUUCACAAUGGCCAUGAAUGCUUUUGGUGACAUGACCAAUGAAGAAUUCAGGCAGAUGAUGGGUUGCUUUCGAAACCAGAAAUUCAGGAAGGGGAAAGUGUUCCGUGAGCCUCUGUUUCUUGAUCUUCCCAAAUCUGUGGAUUGGAGAAAGAAAGGCUACGUGACGCCAGUGAAGAAUCAGAAACAGUGUGGUUCUUGUUGGGCUUUUAGUGCGACUGGUGCUCUUGAAGGACAGAUGUUCCGGAAAACUGGGAAACUUGUCUCACUGAGCGAGCAGAAUCUGGUGGACUGUUCGCGUCCUCAAGGCAAUCAGGGCUGCAAUGGUGGCUUCAUGGCUAGGGCCUUCCAGUAUGUCAAGGAGAACGGAGGCCUGGACUCUGAGGAAUCCUAUCCAUAUGUAGCAGUGGAUGAAAUCUGUAAGUACAGACCUGAGAAUUCUGUUGCUAAUGACACUGGCUUCACAGUGGUCGCACCUGGAAAGGAGAAGGCCCUGAUGAAAGCAGUCGCAACUGUGGGGCCCAUCUCCGUUGCUAUGGAUGCAGGCCAUUCGUCCUUCCAGUUCUACAAAUCAGGCAUUUAUUUUGAACCAGACUGCAGCAGCAAAAACCUGGAUCAUGGUGUUCUGGUGGUUGGCUACGGCUUUGAAGGAGCAAAUUCGAAUAACAGCAAGUAUUGGCUCGUCAAAAACAGCUGGGGUCCAGAAUGGGGCUCGAAUGGCUAUGUAAAAAUAGCCAAAGACAAGAACAACCACUGUGGAAUCGCCACAGCAGCCAGCUACCCCAAUGUGUGAGCUGAUGGAUGGUGAGGAGGAAGGACUUAAGGACAGCAUGUCUGGGGAAAUUUUAUCUUGAAACUGACCAAACGCUUAUUGUGUAAGAUAAACCAGUUGAAUCAUUGAGGAUCCAAGUUGAGAUUUUAAUUCUGUGACAUUUUUACAAGGGUAAAAUGUUACCACUACUUUAAUUAUUGUUAUACACAGCUUUAUGAUAUCAAAGACUCAUUGCUUAAUUCUAAGACUUUUGAAUUUUCAUUUUUUAAAAAGAUGUACAAAACAGUUUGAAAUAAAUUUUAAUUCGUAUAUAAAGGUGGGCCUUUUUUUAAUGCAUUGGCUUUUUGUGUAGUCAGGAAAUAUAAUUAAGCUCUGAAAUAAUAACUUCAUGUGCCAAUGGUAUGUUAGGAGAAAGAUGCUAGCAGAAAGCUGGCUUCCUGGCUCUUGAGUAGUUAUAAAAAUACAGACUUUAUAUCAGCUGCCCAGUUACUGUGUGUUACCCAACUCCUGAAUCUACCAAAAUUUGAUAAACAAUUUGGAAGGACAAACCUACAUUUUUUUUUUUUAUGAGACGGAGUCUCUCUCACUCUGUCACCAAGGCUGGAGUGCAGUAGUGUGAUCUCAGCUCACUGCAACCUCUGCCUCCCGGGUUUAAGCAAUUCUCUGCCUCAGCCUCCCGAGUAGCUGGGAUUACAGGCGCGUGCCACCACGCCUAGUGUAUUUUUAGUAGAGAGAGGGUUUCACCAUCUUGGCCAGGCUGGUCUUGAACUCUCGACCUCGUGAUCCACCUGCCUCAGCCUCCCAAAGUGUUGGGAUUACAGAUGUGAGCCACUGCGCCCAGCCCCUAAAUUGUUUUAGUAAAGAAGAAAGCAGUUGACUUUUUAGAAAAGGAAAUGUCUUCUUCCUUUGACACAUAACCUCAAGAUGGUUAGGUUACGUGAUAAAAAGUGAAGCUGCUUGUUACUGGAGCCUCUCUGAAUUGCUGGUGACCACUUUGCAGUCUGAGGAAGACGCAGGUGCAAGUAAGUUACCAAGGGUAUUUUGUUUUCAUUCCAAGUCUCUGAUGACAUAUUCCACCUAGCUCUUCUAGAAAAGCUUAUUUGUUAACUAGUGUUAGCAAAAAUAAAUGGUGUGGUUAACAAAUCUCAGGCAUUUGACAGUAGCUGGAGAAAUUUGUUCAAGGUCCACAAGAGAUGAGGCUGGGCUACAAAAAGAGGCCUCUGGCCGAAGAUGGAUAAGAGAUCACAAGUGAAAGGUCAGAAGUCACUAGGCCAGACUCUGGCUACCUAAUCCCUGAAUUAAAAAUAAACUCAAAAUGGGGGGAAAAAGGCUAAGCAUAUAGUUACACAGGUAGUAAAUACAAAUAAAACGAUAUUUUUGCAUAUUUAAAAUACUGGAAGAAAGUACACCAAACUUGUGGGUGAAUUAUGGGUGGUUAUUUAACUCGUUUAGUGAAAAGCAUGUAUUUUUAUGAGCAGGAGAAAAUAGUAAAGAUAUACCCACAUUCUGCAGGCUAAAGGAGAGCCCUGUGUGUGUUUUAAAAGCCCAUGUUUCCAGUCAAAUAAAAAAUUACCGGGGAUGAGCUGGUGAAAUUUAAUCGAAAGGUGAUCCAUUGUGAAUGCAAUGGGAGGGAAGGGGCAUGUGGGACUGUGUAUCCCAAAAACCCUUUGAUAGCCUAUGUCCACAGCCAUCUCUGGAAAAUCCAGUCUACCAUAUUCAGUCUUGAGUUUUCUCUGAGAAAGGAUUCCUUCGUCUUUGCAGCAGCAGGCUAAGUUGGUACUCUCCACAGAUUCUUGGAACAACAACCCAGGCUCUAAGGAAACAUCUAGGCACUAAAUUGAAUGAAAGAGUGAUGGCUUUUUAUUCAAAUAAAAAAAUUUCAAAUCUGUCAAAACAGCACCCCUCGGAAAACUAAAAUAGAGAUAUUUCAAGAUUUUAUAAUUUUCAAAGACCUUUGAAAUAUUUUAAACUUGUGAAAAGUUACAAACCUGAUGUGUUGUCUAAAAGCGUUUUUCAAACAAGCCAGUAGACUUGAAAAAUCUAGUCUGAAGCACAGACUUAACCAAUAUUUGCUGGGGAUAUGCCCCCAAAUCUGGCCAUAAACAAAAUCUCUGCAGUACUGUGACAGGUUCAUGAUGGCCAUGACGCCAUGCUGAAGGUUUACCGGAAUGAGAGCAAGGAACACCUGGACCACCCAGGGCGGGAAAACGGCUUAAAGGCGUUCCUAAACUACAAACAAUAGCAUGAGCGAUCUGUGCCUUAAGGACAUGUUCCUGCUGCAGAUAACUAGCCAGACCCCAUGCCUUUGUUUCGUUUGGGAAGGAAUACUUUUAGUUAAUCUAUAAUCUAUAGAAACAAUGUUUAUCACUGGCUUGCUGUCAAUAAACAUGGGUAAAUCUCUGUUCGGGGCUCUCAGCUCUGAAAGCUGUGAGUCCCCUGAUUUCCCACUCUGCAUGCUAUAUUUCUGGGUGUGUGUCUUUAAUUUCUCUAGCGCCUCUGGGUUAGGGUCUCCAUGACCAAGCUGGUCUCGGCAAAUAUUUCCUAUACUCGAACAUCUAAAUUGUUUGUUUUCUUACUUGAAUUGCAAAGGAAGUAAGGAAGGGUGAGAUAGAAAUCACUGAGCAUAUUAAGAGGGAGGAGUUUGCUGAUGUGGGAGUGUAGUUAUGACACUUGGGCAUCAUACUAGAGGCUAUGGACUUAGCAAUAAGGAAACAUCCACUCAGCCCUAUGUGUGGUUCAUGUGUAUGUUUUGCCUAUGAAAGUUGAAACUGUUUUCUAAAUGUUAUUUCCUUUUGUAACUGAUAAAAUUUCUAAAAAGCAAAGAAGAAACUUUUCUGUAUUAAAAAUAACAAACAUUAGUAAAUGUAUAUAUACAGUCAUGUGUUGCUUAAUGAUGGGGAUACAUUCUGAGAAAUGUGUCUUGGGUGAUUUCAUCGUGACGUGAACAUCAUAGAGUACACUGACACAAACCUAGAUGGUAUAGCCUAUUACACACCUAGGCUAUAUGGUACAGCCUGUUGCUCCUAAGCUACGCACCUGUGCAACACAUCACUGUGCUGAGUACUGUACACAGUUGUAACACAGUGGUAAGUAUUCGUGUAUCUGAACAGAAAAGUACAGUAAAAAUAUAGGAUCAUAAUUUUAUGGGACCACUAUCAUAUAUGCAGUCACUGACCAAAACAUCACACAGCACAUGACUUGUGUGUAUGGAUAUCUCAAUUGUAAACAAUUUCACAAAUGUUCAUUAUCUCUUUUUAAGUAAGUUAAUAAGUAAAACUAUUACUAAGCUGCAA